AACCCAAGGUGGAGAGCUGGAUUCCGGCGGGCGGCGCUUGGAGCAGGUGGAGAGGCGUCCUCUUUCCGGCUGUUGCUGCUCUUCUUCCUCCAAUCCUGGGUCUCAGUCAGGGAAGAACGAACAUUCUUCCUUUGCUGCUGGAGCUUUAGAGAACUGUUGCCCAGCACCUAGGCACUUCAGACAUUUCAUCUCACUCAUUUUUGUAAUUUCACUGUAAAAAUCACCUGCACAUUUAUAACACUGUGACUCUCCACUUCUGCUCAAUGCUGAGAAGGGGUCCGCAUACUGCGGGGAGCUGUCUAAGGUGCUGAAGCUUCCCAAGCAUCAGUCUACACCAACACCAUGCGGGGUUAGAUUGUACAUUUUCAUUCUGUCUUUCUGGUUCCCCAUGCCUUGGAUAAGACUAUUUUCAGGAUCGUGAAUAUCUCUCCGUAUCAUGGCCCACGUGAGACACUUUCGGACAUUAGUUUCGGGAUUUUACUUCUGGGAAGCAGCACUGUUACUCAGAAUCCAGAGUCCUCAGACAGUGCUCGACACAUUGUACAUUUUCAAAACCUAUUUGAAGAUGAAAAUGAUUUGGUUGCCACAAAGGAAACAGACAGUGCAAGAUCUCGAAGUGCUCCAAUGUCACCUUCUGAUUUUCUGGAUAAAUUAAUGGGCAGGACAUCAGGAUAUGAUGCAAGAAUCAGACCCAAUUUUAAAGGCCCUCCAGUUAAUGUCACAUGCAACAUAUUCAUCAACAGCUUUGGCUCUAUCGCAGAGACGACCAUGGAUUACAGAGUGAAUAUCUUUCUUCGUCAGAAAUGGAAUGAUCCCCGCCUCGCGUACAGUGAAUAUCCUGACGACUCUUUAGACCUCGACCCCUCCAUGUUGGACUCCAUUUGGAAACCUGAUUUGUUCUUUGCCAAUGAAAAGGGUGCCAACUUUCAUGAAGUCACUACAGACAACAAAUUGCUAAGAAUUUUCAAAAAUGGAAAUGUUCUUUAUUCAAUAAGAUUAACAUUAACACUUUCCUGUCCAAUGGAUCUCAAGAAUUUUCCCAUGGAUGUACAAACAUGUAUAAUGCAACUGGAAAGCUUUGGGUACACAAUGAAUGAUCUCAUUUUUGAAUGGCAAGAUGAGGCACCCGUACAAGUGGCAGAAGGACUCACUUUGCCCCAGUUUCUGUUGAAAGAAGAAAAAGAUUUACGAUACUGCACUAAACAUUACAAUACAGGAAAGUUUACGUGUAUAGAAGUGCGAUUCCAUCUGGAGCGACAAAUGGGAUACUAUCUGAUCCAGAUGUACAUUCCCAGUCUCCUGAUUGUUAUUCUAUCCUGGGUUUCAUUCUGGAUCAACAUGGAUGCAGCACCGGCCAGGGUAGCUCUGGGGAUAACCACUGUGCUAACGAUGACUACACAGAGUUCAGGAUCACGAGCUUCCUUGCCAAAAGUUUCAUAUGUCAAAGCUAUUGAUAUUUGGAUGGCAGUAUGCCUCCUUUUUGUGUUUUCAGCACUUCUGGAGUAUGCAGCUGUAAAUUUUGUAUCAAGACAACACAAAGAACUUCUGAGAUUUCGACGAAAGAGAAAGAAUAAGACAGAAGCUUUUGCACUGGAGAAGUUUUACCGUUUCUCAGAUAUGGAUGAUGAGGUAAGGGAAAGCCGAUUCAGCUUCACAGCCUAUGGAAUGGGACCAUGUCUACAAGCAAAGGAUGGCAUGACUCCAAAGGGCCCCAACCACCCUGUCCAGGUAAUGCCAAAAAGUCCUGAUGAAAUGAGGAAGGUCUUUAUCGACCGGGCCAAGAAGAUUGAUACCAUCUCCCGAGCCUGCUUCCCAUUAGCUUUUUUGAUUUUUAAUAUUUUCUACUGGGUUAUCUAUAAAAUUCUUAGGCAUGAGGAUAUUCAUCAGCAGCAAGAUUAAGUCUCUGGGGGCAUGCAAAUGCAAAUGGUCAAUUCAGAAGAAAGUGUCUCUGCCAUAGGUGUGUAUGUGUAUAUGUGUGCGUGUGGUAUACAAAUGAUGACCAUUGUAUUAAAAUGGCAUAUGGAAAAGCUUUGUAUUUUGGUUAGCUAUGCAAAGUCAUGAGAAAGAUGAGAUUCUUUUAAUGAAUAUAAAAUAUUUAUUAGGGGAUUCUAUUUCAUAUUAAUUCCAGGUGAUUUGUUUUUUCACAGUAAACCAUGUAAGUGGAAGCUUUACUGCCAAUGUGUUUAUAUGUUAUAUAAUAUCUCAUAAUAGUAGACAUGAAAACUACUUUGAAAUUCCUUGAUUUGUAAUUCAAUGCUAUUAAAUCAUACAAAAGCAAAUUUUGCACAGUAAACCAAUAGUUUGAGAUUUAAAACUAUUUUCUUAUAGUAUAGUUACAAAAUGGGAAAAUAAUUAGUUACAGUGGGAAAUUCACUCAUAUUAAUGGAGGAUUGUACAUAUAAAUACUAUUUAAACAACAUAUGUAAUUUUGAAAAUUUUUAAAUAAGAGCAUUAAAAGACUUUAAUGAUUUGGAAUACUAAAUUUAAUUGUUUAGAAUAUUAAGUUUUCCUCUGUGCAAAUUUAAAACAAAUAACAAGAGAUCGUGUUACAGUCACAAUCUACUUUUCUUAAACUUUGUAUCUCUAGGAACGAAGGUGGAAAUACGGGAAACAACUUUGUUUUUAAAUAAGUAUUAUAGCUAUGUAUUUUUAGUUAUUGCCAAACAUUGAACAAUUCAAGCCAGCACCCUUGUUUUUGUUAGACUUUUAAUAGCUACUUAACUGUAUGUGAUUGUGUUUAAUAAUUUGAUAUAACAGGACAAAAUUCAGUAAGACUUUUAUAUUUUAGUUUAGAAUGUGACUUUAAAAUUCAAUGGGAUUAAAGUAUUUACAUUUUGAUAAAAAUGAAUACAAUGAAAACAAAAUGGAUUCAUGGAAGAUUUUUUAAUAAAAACCAUUUUCCCAUCAAUGUUUUAUGGGUCUCAACUCCUAUCUCCAAAUAUAAGUAGGGAAAGUUUUAAUUUUAAAUGAUAUAAGUAAGUCAUUUCUAUAAAGUGAGGACUCUUUUUCUAUUUCUGAAUUAAUGAUUUCAAAAUCUAAGCCAUUCGCAAGAUGUGAAUAAUUUUAAAUGAAAUUUUUACAUAAAAUUUUUCAAUGACCCCAUGGGAUUACUUCAACAAAAACAGAGCAUUAGUAACUUGUUUUUUGCAGUGUAAUUGGGUGCAAAUGUAUGAUAGAGUUCUUGGUAAACAGAACCAGACUCUGACUCUUUUUCAGUUUUGCUAUUUUUUUAACUAUUUUUACCAUAAAUUUAUUUGGAAAAGCUUUGGAAUGCUUUUUAGGUAUUUUAAUUAUUGGUCAGAUGCACAAACUCAGUCCACCAAAUUAUUCACAGAGAAAACUUUAAAGAUUAAGAAAACAAUGAACUCAGAUGUACAAUAGAAAAGCCAGUUCUUUAACAAGAUGCUAUUUUCUACCCUUCAACCACUUUCAAAUUAAAAGCAAAAACUACCAUUUAAAACUAAAACCUUUACAAUGUUAUUGUACAUCAGCUUAUACAAUUGUAAUUUUUUAAAAUAACAUUUUAAAAAAUAGUAAAUGUUAAGCAGUUUUUGCUAGUAAAAGACCAAGUUCCCCUCCUUUAUAAGUAACUUAAAACAACACUAUAAGGAAAUAAUAUCAUGUUUGGCAUUAUGUGCAAAUGACACAACCAAAAGAAUUUGUUACUCUGUAAGUACCCACGUUGAGGACUGUGCACCUGAAAAUUAAACAUAUGCUUCUUCAUUUGGUGUGUAUUUAACAAAACCAUGGAAACAUAUUCUUGUUCUAAAGAUUAGAGCAAGAUAUGUCAUUUGUAUUCCUUGAGAAUUAGCAGGAGAGUUUGAGGUAAUUAUAAACUACAUCAUCUCGAUGUGUCUCUGAAAUACCUGAAUACGUUUUUCUAUACUUUCCACAUCUUAUUUCAAAAGUUUCCCAACAUUGCUUAAGUGAAUUCUGCCAGGAGCAAACAGAAAUAUAAUGAAUGCAAACAUGCUUACUUCCAAAAGAAAUUCACAGACAUCACUUCUUUCCAUAUUUGAGAAUAUUAUAAAUGUGUCUUUGUUAAAUCAGAAACUUAGAAAGUGAAAAUACCAAACAUGAGACAAUAUUGUCAACAAGGACGUUGGUACAUUAGAAAUCUAUCUCAAAAGUAUUACACUUUCCUUAGGCAUAGUUUUCCUUUCCUAUUAUAUUUGUCACUGUCUUACUGCACUAAGAAAAUACUUUAACAGCUUUCACUCACAAGGCAACAGUGACAAGGUGCAUGUGGCUGAAUCCAAUAUGUUUAAAGGAAUGUGUCUCCUCCUUCGAACUCUUAUAGACCUUUUAAAACUGAAAAAUUACAUUGCAGUUAGCAUCCUGAGAUAAUAUUUGCCUCAAUAAGCCCUGUGUCCAACCAGAAUAUUUUAAAUUAAACCAACCACAAAAUUAUUAAUGGCAAGAAAUUAAAAAUGUGUGCAUAUACAUUAACUACUAAACACACAAAUUGGAAUUCCAAUGUGCAUAUUCUGAAGUAUUUUAAAAUAGCCACAUUAGAAAAUAUGGGAUUUUCAUGUAUGCAGUUUAUAUCAUUUUCUUAAAAAGAAUUAUUUGUAUGUCAAUCAUUGAAAUAUUUGAUUCCAUAGCAUAUGAAUUUAUAGGCUAUCUUAUACAUUAGCAUAUAUGUGCCCAACCUUUUCUUUCUUUCCCAACCAUUAGAAUUGAACUUAAACCAUAAUGAGGCUCUAGAACUUACUUUACAACUUUAAAUAGAUUCAAGAGUCACUGUAUUUUCAAGAAAGCUGAGGGUGUUUAAAACUUCUCCAACCCUUCCAAAAGUUUCUCCAUGGCGCUGGAGACCCCAUCCAACUCUCAGUGGCUAUAUUAGGGAAUCAUCCGGACUGCUCAUCUUAUUCUAAAAUUAAUUCUUAUUCUGUUGAUAUAUUCUAAUAACUUUUAUCUUAAUUUGGAAUUUAAUUGCUUGUAUAUUUAUAUAUCCCUAAGACAUGAAUUCAUGUAUUAGUUUAUGAAUACCCAGGAUCUCAUGGAAGGUAAGGGAAAUUUUAGAAAAAAAAAUGAAUAAUCUAAAUGUUUAACUAACAGAAGAGAGCAAGCUGUUCACUACUUUAGUACUCAGUGCAACUUAAGUAGUUAUAAUAUUUGAAAAAAGAUUUAGAUGUAUCUUCCAUACUAUACAUCCCUUUUUCUGAACAUUUUUUAUUCCACUUUUUAAAAUAUGCUUUUCUAUUUUUCUCAACACAACAUACUUCAACCUGCUGGUUACUUGGGAGGACUGAAUAUUAUACUGGCAGCUAAAUUUUUAUUUCAUCUAUAAAGUACACAUUCCAGGAAAUGGACAUGAGAGAAUACAAGAGACUUGCCAAAAUUGAAAUGGAAAAUACUUGCAGUAUUUUGUAAAUGGAAAAGAAGGAAACUGACAGCAUUGUUUUUCACAGGUGUCCCCUAAAAAUUUAGAACACUCUAAGAACAAAACUCUGAGAACAAAAAUGUAUCUAAUGAUCCUUAGACAGAUAUCAUUAACAAUCCUUGAGGUCAUGAUAUCUUCUACUCCAAAAGUGAUUCCACACUCUUUGCAACAUAGAUAAUAGCAUAAACUCCCAAAAUUUAUCAGCAUAUACGACCUAUAUUUUUCAUCUAGUUAAUAUUGAACUAGCAAAGAAAAGCAAGCCAUUCCAAAUAUAAGACAAUCUGGUGUUAAUACAAUAUAUUAGAAGAAAUAGUGUAAAUGUUCACACAGAUUCCCUCUUGCAAAUAAAGUACCCAUAAUACCCAUUGCAUCUUGUACCUGUAUAAGAGACAUCUUCCUCAGCAGAUGCAUUGGUUUUUAUUUCCUUAUUUGUGUGCUACAGUGGUAAAUAUAGCCUCACUGCAUUUUUUUUAUUGUUAUAUAAACCUUUCAUGGAUAAAUAAGCAGUGUACACUGUAAAUUGCAUUAAUUUAAUUAACUUUAAAAUUAAACUUUUAUCUCAGCCCCCAUUCCUCUUUACAAACAUAGUGAUAUUAAAAAGUGAACUUCCAUAGGGAGACACCUGGUACUCCAAUUACUUCAAAAGUAAAGUGAUGCAUAUUCUUCCAUAACAAAGAUACUUAUAGGCCAUGUGUAAAAUAUAACUCUCUACAAUUUAAACGGAACUAGGGCAGGGAAAAAUAUCCUGGGGAAGCUUCUUCCAGAUAUGAGGACAAGAGAUAUAAUCCCAAGUUAGUAGCUAGGACCCACUUACCUGUUUUUUUGGUCUACAUUUUACAUCUUAAUAAUGCCUUCAUCUCUUCCCUUUCCCUCUCUCUCUCUCUCUUUCACACACACACACACACACACACACACACACACACACAUACACAUAUUGGUAAUGAGAUGAAUUCCUUUAGAUUAAAAAUACAAAGACAGUCAAUUUUUCUAGACAAAGGUUCAUAAUCCUGUGAUAUGUUUUGCAAUAUUAAGUGAUUCCUGGUGGAAAAUAUGAACCAUGCAGUCAUUCGAUUUGGCCAGCUCUUAAUCAUGCAACAAUCUUUUGCCUCAAAAACACAUAAACAAAGCUAACUGGAUCAAGUCUUUAACCCUUAACAAUCGAAUUCUAAAACACUAUUUGAACCGUUUUUGAAGAACAGCUAAAUAACUGUCAAAAACCUUUUUCAAAAGACAGCUAGUAAUAUUGGAUGACUUUGUAGUGUCUGAACAGGUGGUUUUCUCAGUAGUUUUUGUGGUUAACACAUAAACAAAGAGGAGACAUUUAAGGUGAUGGAGUAUUAUUUUUAAAAAGUGAUUUUGAACCCUGGCUAUGUGUUGGAAUUCCUUACACAUUUUAAAAAUACAUACAUAUGCUUGGUGUCCAACAUAGAAGAUUAUGAUUUAAUCAUUGAUUAAACAAAUAUUCAUUGAGUACCUUAUGUGUGCCUGGCACUGUCCCAAGUGCUAAAUUUAGUAUUUUUGGAAUAAGAUCUGAAAUUCUGGAUGAUUGAAAAAAUUCCAGAAGUGAGAGAAUUCGUGUGAACUUACACAAGCUUAUUCUCUUAAUAAGGAUCAAUUUAACACUUUUUAAGUUUUAUCAUUUUUUCUUUCUUCAAGCAACUAAUUUUAGUUGUCUCUCAUUUAUAUUCUUAGAAUUAAAAAUAGGCCCGGCCAGGUGGCUCACGCCUGUAAUCCCAGCACUUUGGGAGGCCGAGGCAGUCAAAUCACUUGAGGUCAGGAGUUAAGACACCAGCCUGGCCAAUAUGAUAAAACCCUGUCUCUACUAAAAAUACAAAAAUUAGCCAGGCAUGAUGGCAGGUGCCUGUAAUCCCAGUUACUCAAGGGAGGCUGAGGUGGAAGAAUGGCUUGAGCCCAGGAGAUGGAGGUUGCAGUGAGCCAAGAUCGCACCACUGCACUCCAAACUGGGUGACAGAGUGAGACUCUGUCUCACAAACAAACAGACAGACAAAAAAAGAAUUUAAAAUAAAUCUUUGAUGCGUUUCAAUUCAGCUUUCCUCCCAAUGUCAGAAUCUUCACCAUUACAUUAUCCACAUUCUUCGAGCACCCAGAUAGCAACAGGUAGCUCAUUACUCUGAGGGCAGUCUUCUGUUCCAUUGUGACAUAACUCUAGAUGAUAAAAAUGUUAAUCUUCAUCAAGAAAUGACUUUUACUUCCUAAAAUACCAAGUAAGUUUAUUCCCCUCCUAUAAGACAACUAGCAUAUAUUUUCACAUUUCUGCUGUCUGUGUUUAAGUUCAAUCAACCCCUUAUCACUAGCUUUAUUCUUAUUUAAACCAUUCAUGAGAGCAUUGUAAGUGUUAAACAAUGAUGAGAUAUUUUCAGGCUUAUAAAAUAAUGAAAUAUAAAAUUAAUUAUCUACAUAGAUAAAUAGAAAUUGAUGAAAAUUUCUAUGUAUAUUAUUUUCAGUAACUGUUAAUGUCUUCCUAUAACAGCAAUAAAUUUAAAUUAAAUAUUUUUAAAUUUAUUUCAGAUAUGAAGAUAUUAUAUAAAACUCUACAAAGUAAUAUGAAUUUAAAAAAACUAGCAGCAAACCAUAUUAACCAUAUUGUGUGUUUUUAGAGUAAAGCUAUAACAAAAGUACAGGGGAUUAAGUUGUUUUAUUUUAAUAGCUGCUUUUACUCUGGGGUGGUUUUAGCAAUGGCGCCUUUGGGCAACCCCGCUCACAUACACAGUAUCCAGCCUGGGUGGUUAAUACUAGGGAGCUGUGACUUAAAUGGCAGGAAAGGAUUCAGAUGUAAAAUUGUACUUGAAUAUGCUUGAAUAAUUUUGCACUUCUUCACUUUUUUCUCUAUGAAUUAUUCAAUGGUCAUUACUUAAAUUUGUAUUUUAAUGUAUGAUAAAUGAUAAUAUGGGGGGGGAAAUAGAGUGAAGUACCCUGACAUUCUACAGAUAUAAUAUGAUAUGCUAUGAAAAACAAAACAAAAAGAAAAUGUGCCAUAUAUUUUCCAUGUACCAUCUUUAUAUGAUAUACAGUGACUUCAUUAUUAGUGAGUCAAGUUGUUUAAAGGACUACCAAAAGAAGUAUUGCUAUUUUAUGGUUUUUAUGGUGUAAAUUAUUUUUCUGUCUUCUUGAGUCUUAUGUCUAAGUCUGUCUUCCUUGUCCAGAUGCUGUCAUAUUUUUCCAGGAAAUUAUACUGAAAACAUAUUUAAAAAUUUAUGCACGAUUUCAUCAACUUGUUUUUCAUUAUAUUAUAUUUAGUUCAAUUUUGCAACUAACAGACUCUCUAUCAGAGUCAUUAACCUGUGAACAGUAUAAAGUAUUUAACAUGUAACUAUAGAUAAUUUGAUCCGAAACAAUAAAAAUGAACACUUUUCAAGAA